CCUUUUCCUUUUUACCCAUUUGAUUGUCUUGAUUUUUGAUUUUCAUUUCAGUUUUGUUUUGUUUUGUUUUUGCUGUUGACUUUUUGGUCCUUUUUCCUCCUUCCCUUUCCUGCCCUGUCUUCCAAAUCCCUAAAAAGGUCUCUGGGGACGUAACAGAAAGUUGGGUGGGUCAAGUGACAGGAAGAGAUGUCAGGGAGAGGCCAGAGCUGGCAGGGACACAGCUGGAAGGGCAGAGGAGCACCUGGGCAGAAAGGAGCUGGGACAGUGGAGCCCAGGGGAGAGGGUCGGGCAAGGGAGGGGUGGGAGAGGCUGCCCGCAGGAGCCAUGGCUGCAGGAACUUAAAAGAUUGAUCAGCUCCCCUUACCUUGGCCCCAAAUUUGGCCAAACGGGCUAGAGAGAGCCCUGCACAAAAGCACUGGAUGGGAGUGUAUUGGGGGGUUCCACCUCCCCUGCCCAAUGUCCCUGUGGGUAUUUUAACUCUUGGGCUCCCUGGAGGUGAAUGAAUGACCACAAAGUCCGUGGUGGUAUAUCUGUUCCCUCCAGAAUCCAUUCCUUCCCUUCUCUCCCUUUCUUCCUUGGCUCCCAGCAUCCGGAGUAGGGAAGAGAAGGAAAGGAAAAGGAAGGGAAAGUGAGGAUGAGGCUAGGAUGGGGAGAAGGAGGAUCUGCUCAAUUCACUUAGUCCCCCUGGGUGACACACAGGACCGCUGUGGCGUCCAGGCGGCAGGAUGCUGGGCACCUGCCCUGCCGCUCCUGACUUGCUGUGUGGCCUUGAGCAGAUCCACUCCCUGCCCAGAGCUAAGUCUCCUCAUUUGCAAAUUAGGGCUAAUAAUGGGCACCUGGCAGGGCCUUUGUGCGCACUGGUAGGUAUACAGGCAGACAAACAAUGAAGACACACCCAGUUGCAUUACAAAGGAGAGGUGUGUAAGGUCAUAGUGGGAGGUUAGGGCAGGAAGGUUCAGACCAGGAAGAGGUCUAUUCCAGCUUUGGAGCAGCCAGGAGGCCUUCCUAGAGGAGGGGGCACUUGGGCUGGGCUCUGGAGGGCCCUAGAUUUUAGUCGGGAGGCCCCUGGGGCUUGGAGCAGGGCCACUGCAUGGAGACUAGAAAAUGAAGGGAGGCCAGAGGCCGGGCUGGGGCAGAGGAGGCUGCAGCAAUUUCUGGCAACAAAGACGGGGGGCACCCUUGAGGAUCAAAUCAUCGAGGCCAACCCUGCCAUGGAGGCCUUUGGCAACGCCAAGACCCUGAGGAAUGAUAACUCCUCCCGCUUUGGCAAGUUCAUCCGCAUUCACUUUGGUCCCUCUGGGAAGCUGGCAUCCGCGGAUAUUGACAGCUAUCUCCUGGAGAAGUCGCGGGUGAUCUUCCAGUUGCCUGGUGAGCGCAGCUACCAUGUCUACUACCAGAUCCUCUCAGGGAGGAAGCCAGAGCUGCAGGACAUGCUGCUUCUGUCUAUGAACCCCUAUGACUACCACUUCUGCAGCCAGGGCGUCAUCACCGUGGACAACAUGAAUGAUGGGGAGGAGCUCAUCGCCACCGACCAUGCCAUGGACAUCCUAGGCUUCAGCGUGGAUGAGAAAUGUGCCUGCUAUAAGAUCGUGGGCGCCCUCCUGCACUUUGGCAACAUGAAGUUCAAGCAGAAGCAGCGGGAGGAGCAGGCGGAGGCCGAUGGCACUGAGAGUGCUGACAAGGCUGCCUACCUGAUGGGGGUCAGCAGUGGGGACCUCCUCAAAGGCCUUUUGCACCCCCGGGUGCGUGUAGGGAACGAGUACGUGACCAAGGGCCAGAGUGUGGAGCAGGUGGUGUUUGCUGUGGGGGCUCUGGCCAAGGCCACCUAUGACCGGCUGUUCAGGUGGCUGGUGUCUCGGAUCAACCAGACCCUGGACACAAAGCUGCCCCGGCAGUUCUUCAUCGGGGUUCUGGACAUCGCUGGGUUUGAGAUCUUUGAGUUCAACAGCUUCGAACAGCUGUGCAUCAACUUCACCAAUGAGAAAUUGCAGCAGUUCUUCAACCAGCACAUGUUUGUGCUGGAGCAGGAGGAGUACAAGCGGGAGGGCAUCGACUGGGUCUUCAUCGACUUCGGCCUUGACCUGCAGCCUUGCAUCGACCUCAUCGAGAAGGUUAGAAGACUGAGGCUUAGUGAUGUCGGAGGGCCCCACAGCUACUCGUUCUGUUCCCAGCCACUGGGCAUCCUGUCCAUCCUGGAGGAGGAAUGCAUGUUCCCCAAGGCCUCAGACGCCAGCUUCCGGGCCAAGCUCUACGACAACCACGCGGGGAAGUCACCCAAUUUCCAGCAGCCUCGGCCUGACAAGAAGCGCAAGUACCAGGCCCACUUCGAGGUGGUCCACUACGCAGGCGUGGUGCCUUACAGCAUUGUGGGCUGGCUGGAGAAAAACAAGGAUCCCCUGAAUGAGACCGUGGUCCCCAUCUUCCAGAAGUCACAGAAUAGGCUCCUGGCGACUCUCUAUGAGAAUUAUGCGGGCUCCUGCUCCACUGAGCCCCCCAAGUCUGGGGUGAAAGAGAAGCGUAAGAAGGCAGCAUCGUUCCAGACGGUGUCCCAGCUGCACAAGGAGAACCUCAACAAGCUGAUGACCAACCUGCGGGCCACACAGCCCCACUUCGUCCGCUGCAUUGUCCCCAACGAGAACAAAACCCCAGGGGUCAUGGAUGCCUUCUUGGUGCUACACCAGCUGCGCUGCAAUGGGGUCCUGGAGGGGAUCCGGAUCUGCCGCCAAGGGUUCCCCAACAGGUUGCUCUACACCGACUUCCGGCAGCGGUACCGUAUCCUGAACCCCAGUGCCAUCCCGGAUGACACCUUCAUGGACAGCAGGAAGGCCACAGAGAAACUGCUGGGCUCGCUGGACUUGGAUCACACCCAGUACCAGUUUGGCCACACCAAGGUCGGGGCACUGUGGGAUCAGGGCUGGCCAUGGCUGUGGCGGUCACACUGGGCAGGGUUCAUGCGGAUGGUUGGGGGUUACCCUGGCUGUCUACCUCUCCGCCCCCAGGUGUUCUUCAAGGCUGGGCUUCUAGGCGUCCUGGAAGAGCUCCGUGACCAGCGCCUGGCCAAGGUGCUGACGCUGCUGCAGGCGCGGAGCCGUGGCCGCCUCAUGCGCCUUGAGUACCAGCGCCUGCUGGGAGGCAGGGAUGCGCUGUUCACCAUCCAGUGGAACAUCCGUGCCUUCAAUGCCGUCAAGAACUGGUCAUGGAUGAAGCUCUUUUUCAAGAUGAAGCCGCUGCUGCGCUCGGCGCAGGCUGAGGAGGAGCUGGCGGCCCUGCGGGCAGAGCUGCGGGGGUUGCGAGGGGCGCUGGCUGCGGCCGAGGCCAAGCGCCAGGAACUGGAGGAGACGCACGUCAGCAUCACCCAGGAGAAGAAUGACCUGGCCCUGCAGCUGCAGGCUGAGCAGGACAACCUGGCAGAUGCCGAGGAGCGCUGCCACUUGCUGAUCAAGUCCAAGGUGCAGCUGGAGGGGAAGGUGAAGGAGCUGAGUGAGCGGCUGGAGGAUGAGGAGGAGGUGAACGCUGACCUGGCCGCCCGCCGGCGCAAGCUGGAGGACGAGUGCACGGAGCUCAAGAAGGACAUUGAUGACCUGGAGCUGACACUGGCCAAAGCUGAGAAGGAGAAGCAAGCCACUGAGAACAAGGUGAAGAACCUGACGGAAGAGAUGGCUGCGCUGGACGAGUCAGUGGCCCGGCUGACCAAGGAGAAGAAGGCGUUGCAGGAGGCCCACCAACAGGCCCUGGGUGACCUGCAGGCCGAGGAGGACCGUGUGAGCGCGCUGACCAAGGCCAAGCUCCGGCUGGAGCAACAGGUGGAGGACCUGGAAUGCUCCCUGGAGCAGGAGAAGAAGCUGCGCAUGGACACGGAGCGGGCCAAGCGCAAGCUGGAGGGUGACCUGAAGCUGACGCAGGAGUCGGUGGCUGAUGCUGCUCAAGACAAGCAGCAGCUGGAGGAGAAGCUCAAGAAGAAGGACUCCGAGCUGAGCCAGCUGAGCCUGCGGGUGGAAGACGAGCAGCUCUUGGGGGCCCAGAUGCAGAAGAAGAUCAAGGAGCUGCAGGCUCGGGCGGAGGAGCUGGAAGAGGAGCUGGAGGCAGAGCGGGCAGCCCGGGCCCGCGUGGAGAAGCAGCGUGCAGAGGCGGCGCGGGAGCUGGAGGAGCUGAGCGAGCGGCUGGAGGAGGCAGGCGGCGCAUCCGCGGGGCAGCGCGAGGGCUGCCGCAAGCGGGAGGCGGAGCUGGGGAGGCUGCGGCGGGAGCUGGAGGAGGCGGCGCUGCGGCACGAGGCCACAGUGGCGGCACUGCGGCGCAAGCAGGCGGAGGGCGCGGCGGAGCUGGGGGAGCAGGUGGACAGCCUGCAGCGGGUGCGGCAGAAGCUGGAGAAGGAGAAGAGUGAGCUGCGCAUGGAGGUGGACGACCUGGCUGCCAACGUGGAGACUCUGACCCGCGCCAAGGCCAGUGCAGAGAAGCUGUGCCGGACCUAUGAGGAUCAGCUAAGCGAGGCCAAGAUCAAGGUGGAGGAGCUGCAGCGGCAGCUGGCGGACGCAAGCACGCAGCGUGGGCGACUACAGACGGAAAGCGGGGAGCUGAGUCGCCUGCUAGAGGAGAAGGAGUGUCUGAUCAGUCAGCUGAGCCGUGGAAAGGCCCUGGCCGCCCAAAGCCUGGAAGAGUUGCGGCGCCAGCUAGAGGAGGAAAGCAAGGCCAAGAGUGCCCUGGCCCACGCCGUGCAGGCUCUGCGGCACGACUGUGACCUCCUGCGGGAGCAACACGAGGAGGAGGCUGAGGCCCAGGCUGAGCUGCAGCGGCUGCUGUCCAAGGCCAAUGCCGAGGUGGCCCAGUGGAGGAGCAAGUACGAAGCAGAUGCCAUCCAGAGGACCGAGGAGCUGGAGGAGGCCAAAAAAAAGCUGGCACUGCGGCUGCAGGAGGCAGAGGAGGGCGUGGAGGCUGCCAACGCCAAGUGCUCAUCGUUGGAGAAGGCCAAGCUGCGGCUACAGACAGAGUCAGAGGAUGUAACCCUGGAGCUGGAGCGGGCGACCUCAGCAGCUGCUGCGCUGGACAAGAAGCAGCGGCACUUGGAACGGGCACUGGAGGAACGGCGGCGGCAGGAGGAGGAGAUGCAGCGGGAGCUGGAGGCGGCACAGAGGGAGUCCCGUGGCCUGGGCACCGAGCUCUUCCGGCUGCGGCACGGCCACGAGGAGGCACUUGAAGCCCUGGAGACGCUCAAGCGGGAGAACAAGAACCUGCAGGAGGAGAUCAGCGACCUCACAGACCAGGUGAGUCUCAGUGGGAAGAGCAUCCAGGAACUGGAGAAAACCAAGAAGGCGCUGGAAGGCGAGAAGAGUGAGAUCCAGGCUGCACUGGAGGAGGCAGAGGGGGCCCUGGAGCUGGAGGAGACCAAGACGCUGCGGAUCCAGCUGGAGCUCUCCCAGGUCAAAGCAGAAGUGGACCGGAAGCUGGCAGAGAAAGACGAGGAGUGCGCUAACCUGAGGCGCAACCACCAGCGAGCUGUGGAGUCCCUGCAGGCCUCCCUGGAUGCAGAGACACGGGCCCGCAAUGAGGCGCUGCGGCUCAAGAAGAAGAUGGAGGGUGACCUCAACGACCUGGAGCUGCAGCUGGGCCAUGCCACCCGUCAGGCCACAGAGGCCCAGGCUGCCACGCGGCUGAUGCAGGCACAGCUCAAGGAGGAGCAGGCAGGGCGGGACGAGGAGCAGCGGCUGGCAGCUGAGCUCCACGAGCAGGCGCAGGCUCUGGAGCGCCGGGCCUCGCUGCUGGCUGCGGAGCUGGAGGAGCUGCGGGCUGCCCUGGAGCAGGGCGAGCGCAGCCGGCGACUGGCAGAGCAGGAGCUUUUGGAGGCCACCGAGCGCCUCAACCUUCUGCAUUCGCAGAACACAGGCCUCCUAAACCAGAAGAAGAAGCUGGAGGCGGACUUGGCCCAGCUGAGCGGGGAGGUGGAGGAGGCUGCACAGGAGAGGCGGGAGGCUGAGGAGAAGGCCAAAAAGGCCAUCACUGAUGCGGCCAUGAUGGCCGAGGAGCUGAAGAAGGAGCAGGACACAAGUGCACACCUGGAACGGAUGAAGAAGACGCUGGAGCAGACGGUGCGCGAGCUCCAGGCCCGCCUUGAGGAGGCAGAACAGGCCGCCCUCCGUGGCGGGAAGAAGCAGGUGCAGAAGCUGGAGGCCAAGGUACGGGAGCUGGAGGCUGAGCUUGAUGCAGAGCAGAAGAAGCACGCCGAGGCCCUUAAGGGCGUGCGCAAGCAUGAGCGCCGUGUCAAGGAGCUCGCAUACCAGGCCGAGGAGGACAGGAAGAACCUGGCUCGCAUGCAGGACCUGGUGGACAAGCUGCAGAGCAAGGUCAAGAGCUACAAGCGCCAGUUUGAGGAGGCGGAGCAGCAGGCCAACACCAACCUGGCCAAGUAUCGCAAGGCCCAGCACGAGCUGGAUGAUGCGGAGGAGCGGGCAGACAUGGCGGAAACCCAGGCCAACAAGCUGCGGGCACGGACCCGGGACGCCCUGGGCCCCAAGCUAUCCCUUUCUCCUCAGCACAAGGAGUGACGGCCUGACCCCCUGGGCUCUAAAGAGGAAUGUCUGCUGUUGCACAUCUGGCUGAGGCCACCUGCCCCGAUCCUGCCAUCUCUGCAUCGCCCCCUGCUGCCUUCAGCCUUCCCUGGGCCCUGAAUAAACACCACAGCCAGUUUCCUUCUCAUUCUUUUCUUUGGGGUUCAGGAGGAAAAACACAGUCCUAGGGACAAAAGCCAGGUCCACAGCAGUCAUUUUUAAAAUAAAGUUAUUUAAUAGUCUCCA